UCCUGAAUGCUUGUUUGCUACUUGUGGGACUUAAUAUUUGCCUAAGGGUAAAAAGAUACACUUUUUCUGGAGACCAAACAACAUAAACCUCACUGUCAAGACACCACUCAUUUUAUGAAGGAAGAUGAAAUAGAAAAUUUUAAUCUGCUAUCAUGGAUAGGAAAAAAUUUUCAAUUCCCAGCUUUAGCCUCUUUUUUGCAUCUGCCAGGAAAUUGGAUGGCUCUCAACUCUCAAGAUAAAUUUCAUAUUGCAGUUGUAAUAUUUUGUGCGUAUAUUGAGGAUACACAAACAAUAAAACCUAGGAAAGAUGAGGGUGGAAAGAGGACAUUUGAUUGAAAACAUACACAUAAGUUUAAGAUGCCAGUAUGUUUUCAAUCUUUAUUAAGCUUAAUUUAUAUACCAUAAAGUUUAUGCAUUUAAAAUACACAAUUCUAAAAUUAGCUGGGCGUGGUUGUGCAUACCUGUAAUCCCAGCUACUUUGGAGGCUGAGGCAGGAGAAUCACCUCAACCCGGGAGGUGGAGGCUUCAGUGAGCUGAGAUUGCAUCACUGCACUCCAGCCUAGGCAACUGAUCAACACUCCAUCAAAUAAAUAAAUAAAUAAAUAAAUAAAGUAUACAAUUCAGUGGUUUUGUUUUUUUUUUUACUAUCCUUACAGAGCUGCUCUGAUGCUCAGGGAAUCUGCUGGUAACUUAACUCUGUUUUCUUUCAUUUUUUUCUUUUUUGAGACAGUCUUGAUCUGUCGUCCAGGCCGGAGUGCUGUGGCACCAUUUCAGCUCACUGCAACCUCUGUCUCCUGGGUUCAAGCGAUUUUCCUGCCUUCGCCUCCCGAGUAGCUGGGAUUACAGGCAUCUGCUACCAGGCCUGGCUAAGUUUUGUAUUUUUAGUAGAGACACGGGGUGGGGUUUCACCAUGUUGGCCAUGCUGAUCUCCAACUCCUGACCUCAAGUGAUACACCCGUCUUGGUCUCCCAAAGUGCUGGGAUUACAGGCGUGAGCCACUUUGUCCAGCCCUGUUUUCAUGACCACCGAAAAUCCUCCUCACCUAGGUCAGCUCUCCUCACAAAUCUGGCCAUUGAUCACAAAGAGAUCAAAUGAAAGCUCAGGUUGCACCUUAACAAUUCCAACAGCAACAGCAAAAGAAGGGUUCAAAGUCCUGGCCAACUAAACCAUGGGUCACUUUUAUCCACUUUUACACAUGUGCCCUCUCUAAAGCACACAUGUAAACAGAGGAUAAAACCUAACUUGGUUGGGUGCAGUGGCUCACAUCUGUAAUCCCAGUGCUUUGGGGAGGCUGAGAUAGGAGGAUCACUUGAGGCCAGUAGUUUGAGAUAAGCCUGGGCAACAUGGCUAGACCCCAUUGCUACAAAAAAUUAAAAAAUUAGCUUAGUGUGGUGGUGUGUGCCUGUGGUCCUAGCUACAUGGAAGGCUGAAUCGGGAGGAUUGCUUGAGCCCAGGAAUUUGAGGUUGCAGUGAGUUAUGACUGCACCAUUACACUCCAGCCUGGGUGACAGAGCAAGUCCCUGUCUCUAAAACAAAAACAAAAACAAAACAAAACAACAAAAAAGAAAAAACAAAAAAAAUAAAAAACUCACUAAGCAGCUUUAUGCUUUAAAGCAGGGGUUCCCAGACCCCAGGCUGUGGACCAGUAAUGGUCAGUUGCCUGUUAGGACCUGGCUGCACAGCAGGUGAGGGGCAGGGGAGGGAGCAUUACUGCCUGAGCUCUGCCUCCUGACAGAUCAGCAGAGGCAUUUGAUUCUCAGAGGAGGGCUAACCCUAUUGUGAAUGGAGUAUGUGAGGGAUGUGGGUUGUGUGUUCCUUAUGAUAAUCUAAUGCCUGAUGAUCUGAGGUGGAACAGUUCCAUGAAGCUGGUCCCUGAUGCCAAAAAGUUUGGGGACCACUGCUUUAAAGAACACAAAGGAUUUUCAGGUAGUAUCUGCUGGAAGCCAGGGGAGGGGGUAAUUUUGGGGGCAAUAACACAAAGGAAAUGAAAACAAUCACUUAUUUUAACUACAGCAUGGAUCCAACUUAUUCAUUUGUUGUGGAAACACACACACACACACACACACAUACACAUCACAGGCAAUAUUUUGGCUGUUACUCUUAAUGGAAUCUAGGCCUUUUCCAUCUAACCAUAAAACUUACUAGCACUCUUGGCUCCAGGCAGAUUUCCAGUCCCCCUAGGCAAGCCUUUGUACUAUAGCCAGCUGCAGGCAGUAGCUUCCAUCAAGCUCCCUGGUAUUUGAAGUGGCAAGCCACUAAACUUGGCAUGCCUCUGGUGCAUGUUCACACAGACUGGGUGUCUGUUUAUCUCCCUGAAUUAUUUCUCUCAAAUCUUGUGCUCCCUCAACCCCUAUCUUGAAGUUUGGAAAACUACUGAUUUGGUCAUUAUCUUUUUCUUUGAUCAGUGAGUCACCUUAGCAGGUCUAUUUAGGUUAAAAAGUCACUCUGGUGCCUGGUUUAUUAUCUCGAUUGGUUAUUACAUUGAGUAAUCAGAUAAUGGCUUAACUUCAAUUUCCAUUUGUGGUCUAUUAAUAUAACCUUGAAACAGAUUUAAACCCAGCUAUAACUUUUUAUUUCAUGCUUUUACAAAUAAUGUGUUCAUGUGUUUUUUAUCCUCCAGCAUCCAGAUUUUUAUCUUUAAAUACCAUCUCCCACUAAAAGGAACCAGAGCUCUCUGGAGAAAUGGCUGAUUCCACAACUGGGGCAGGAAAUGUAUCAGGUAAGUCUGGAAGAAAAUAAUGGAGAAAAGAAGAGUGGGAAGAGUGAUGCAGAUGAAACAAGAUUGACAUGAUUUGAUAAUUGCUGAAAUAGGGUGUUGGGUACACAUGGGAGUUCUUUAAAGUAUUCUUUUAUAUAUUUUAAACUUUUUCCAUAAAAAUAGUUUAAGGAAAGUUAAAAAUGUUAUUUUUUAAACUGAAGGAGUAAUAGCGCCCUUUGUAGAAACAAAAGAUUUCUACAAAGAAAAGUAAAGUCUCCCUCCUACUCCAGACCCUCGCACACCUCUUCAGGGCAAUCCUAGUAACAAUUUCCCGUGUAUUUGUCAAGAAAGUUUCCAUGAAAAUAUAUUUUUUAAAUGUACAUACUCAUAAAUACAAACAUUUUUAAAACCACAAAUGGUAGCGUAUUAUACACAUUAUUUUAUGCCUUAUGAAGUUUUAUUUCCCAUUUUAAUACAAUGAAGAUGUCUACACAUUACAAUAUUGUGGAUUUUUAUGCUUUACAAUUGAGCUUCUUCCUUCGAGUUUCUUUGAUCUAAUCAAGAGAUAGAAGGCCUCCAGCUUCACAUUCCUCACGAUUAUUUACAAAAAGAAGGAUGGCUCAGCCAAGGCUAAAUUUAGGUUACAGUCCCUAAUCUUAACACAGUUUUUAAGUUUAGGUUUCAGCUUUUGGGAUAUUAUUGUUACCUUGAAAAAUGUCACGUUUAAAAACACCUCACACCCUCUACUAUAGAUUGGAUCUUGGGAAAUAGGGUUGAGGACCGGAUCAAUACAAGAAUCCUCAUAACCUCCGCCCCGGCGCGAACCUGGGAGGGCUGCAGACAGUCUAAAGGCUGUGGUGACCUCAGCGCUGCGUCCCUCCAGCAACCGGCGAGUGCUGGGGCACAGGCCAUACCCCCCUAAGCUCGGCAUCGCCUGCACCUCUCACAGGUGCUCUGUCCGCCACAGUAACGCACUAUGGAAAGGAAAGUUGUACGGCGAACGACUGAAGGAGCCAAACGAGGUGGAUCUGGAGCGGCCGCAAGGUGCCUGUGCUGCUGGCUUUUAACACACAAUAAGAGUGCCAAGGGAUACAAGAAGCCACAGGGGGAAAAACAAGUGACAUAUCUGCAUGGAGCCUAAAUUUCGCUUGGUGAUUUUCAGGGUAGAAGCAUUACAUAUUAAAAACACUGCUAUUUUAGGGGAAUACAGAAUUUAAAAAUCCACACAGAUUCGCAACAUAAAACAUGCCGCCCAAAGACACGUCCGCGGUGUCCCGACAGUUCCGGCUCCGCCCGCGGGCCACGAGGCGGGGAGCGACGGUCACUCCCCUCGGUUACCCGGAGUACUUGGGCGGGAACGGGUAGCUCGCGGGAGAGACGGGCUCCUGGGCGAGGGCUGCGUCUUAGUCGCCCUGCUUCUUAGCUCUCGAGGUCCCGCGUGUUACGUGUUAGCACCGCCCGGGGGCGUCAGCAUGACCCGAGGCUGCAGGAACCGUGAACUCUCUGCCCCGCGGGCCCAGGUGACCGCGGGCGGCGCUCUCCCGCGCGCGGGGGGCGGGGCUCCCCCCGGCUGUUCACUCAGCUACCACAGCGACGUAAAAUGGUGUCCGCUAGGCGUCCCAGGACGGCUUCCUGAGGGACUGGAGGGCCCCGACAGCCGGAAAGCCUGCCCCGCCCCUUGGCCGGCACAGGUACGACGGCGGGGAGCUCAGAAGUUUCGAACUCCAAGGGCCGAAGCACAGCCAAACACCCCACGGAACUUAACAAAUGUUUGUGGGGAGAACGCCGAAAACGCGGGGAGGCGGGGCUGGCGCACAGUCACCCUCUCGCGACAUCUAAGUGACGUCGCACAGCAAGCACGUGUUCUAGUCUUUCACCUUCAGUCAGCCUCCUCCGUUAUACAGGCCUACCCCUUUAAGCGAGUGAUGGACAGUUAUUUCAGCCUAUCAACUUCCUUGCCGACAUCCAAUCAGAUUUAAACUUCUUUUAGCCGCCGGAGGAGUUGGAAAAAGGGGGUCGAAAGAGGGAGCUUACCGUCUCU